ACUUUCAGUUUCAUUAGGCUCUGAAGCCAUUACAAAGGUUGCUUAACUUCUAAUUAUUUGAUCACUGAGGAAAAUCCAGAAAGCUACACAACACUGAAGGGGUGAAAUAAAAGUCCAGCGAUCCAGCGAAAGAAAAGAGAAGUGACAGAAACAACUUUACCUGGACUGAAGAUAAAAGCACAGACAAGAGAACAAUGCCCUGGACAUGGCUCCAGAGAUCCACAUGACAGGCCCAAUGUGCCUCAUUGAGAACACUAAUGGGGAACUGGUGGCGAAUCCAGAAGCUCUGAAAAUCCUGUCUGCCAUUACACAGCCUGUGGUGGUGGUGGCAAUUGUGGGCCUCUACCGCACAGGAAAAUCCUACCUGAUGAACAAGCUAGCUGGGAAGAAUAAGGGCUUCUCUCUGGGCUCCACAGUGAAAUCUCACACCAAAGGAAUCUGGAUGUGGUGUGUGCCUCACCCCAAAAAGCCAGAACACACCUUAGUCCUGCUUGACACUGAGGGCCUGGGAGAUGUAAAGAAGGGUGACAACCAGAAUGACUCCUGGAUCUUCACCCUGGCCGUCCUCCUGAGCAGCACUCUCGUGUACAAUAGCAUGGGAACCAUCAACCAGCAGGCUAUGGACCAACUGUAGUAUCCUUUUGUGACCCAGAACAGCACCAAGGUCAGAGGGGACACCUGUAUUCAUAAACCAGCUGCCUGACUGUGAAUCCUGAUGAAUCAAGCUCAAAAGGAGAAAACAAAAAAUAAUGCAAGUACAGAGGAGAGAUCCCAUCUAUGUGACAGAGCUGACACAUCGAAUCCGAUCAAAAUCCUCACCUGAUGAGAAUGAGAAUGAGGAUUCAGCUGACUUUGUGAGCUUCUUCCCAGAUUUUGUGUGGACACUGAGAGAUUUCUCCCUGGACUUGGAAGCAGAUGGACAACCCCUCACACCAGAUGAGUACCUGGAGUAUUCCCUGAAGCUAACGCAAGGUACCAGUCAAAAAGAUAAAAAUUUUAAUCUGCCCCGACUCUGUAUCCGGAAGUUCUUCCCAAAGAAAAAAUGUUUUGUCUUCGAUCUGCCCAUUCACCGCAGGAAGCUUGCCCAGCUUGAGAAACUACAAGAUGAAGAGCUGGACCCUGAAUUUGUGCAACAAGUAGCAGACUUCUGUUCCUACAUCUUUAGCAAUUCCAAAACUAAAACUCUUUCAGGAGGCAUCAAGGUCAAUGGGCCUCGUCUAGAGAGCCUAGUGCUGACCUAUAUCAAUGCUAUCAGCAGAGGGGAUCUGCCCUGCAUGGAGAACGCAGUCCUGGCCUUGGCCCAGAUAGAGAACUCAGCCGCAGUGCAAAAGGCUAUUGCCCACUAUGACCAGCAGAUGGGCCAGAAGGUGCAGCUGCCCGCAGAAACCCUCCAGGAGCUGCUGGACCUGCACAGGGUUAGUGAGAGGGAGGCCACUGAAGUCUAUAUGAAGAACUCUUUCAAGGAUGUGGACCAUCUGUUUCAAAAGAAAUUAGCGGCCCAGCUAGACAAAAAGCGGGAUGACUUUUGUAAACAGAAUCAAGAAGCAUCAUCAGAUCGUUGCUCAGCUUUACUUCAGGUCAUUUUCAGUCCUCUAGAAGAAGAAGUGAAGGCGGGAAUUUAUUCGAAACCAGGGGGCUAUUGUCUCUUUAUUCAGAAGCUACAAGACCUGGAGAAAAAGUACUAUGAGGAACCAAGGAAGGGGAUACAGGCUGAAGAGAUUCUGCAGACAUACUUGAAAUCCAAGGAGUCUGUGACCGAUGCAAUUCUACAGACAGACCAGAUUCUCACAGAAAAGGAAAAGGAGAUUGAAGUGGAAUGUGUAAAAGCUGAAUCUGCACAGGCUUCAGCAAAAAUGGUGGAGGAAAUGCAAAUAAAGUAUCAGCAGAUGAUGGAAGAGAAAGAGAAGAGUUAUCAAGAACAUGUGAAACAAUUGACUGAGAAGAUGGAGAGGGAGAGGGCCCAGUUGCUGGAAGAGCAAGAGAAGACCCUCACUAGUAAACUUCAGGAACAGGCCCGAGUACUAAAGGAGAGAUGCCAAGGUGAAAGUACCCAACUUCAAAAUGAGAUACAAAAGCUACAGAAGACCCUGAAAAAAAAAACCAAGAGAUAUAUGUCGCAUAAGCUAAAGAUCUAAACAACAGAGCUUUUCUGUCAUCCUAACCCAAGGCAUAACUGAAACAAUUUUAGAAUUUGGAACAAGUGUCACUAUAUUUGAUAAUAAUUAGAUCUUGCAUCAUAACACUAAAAGUUUACAAGAACAUGCAGUUCAAUGAUCAAAAUCAUGUUUUUUCCUUAAAAAGAUUGUAAAUUGUGCAACAAAGAUGCAUUUACCUCUGUACCAACAGAGGAGGGAUCAUGAGUUGCCACCACUCAGAAGUUUAUUCUUCCAGACGACCAGUGGAUACUGAGGAAAGUCUUAGGUAAAAAUCUUGGGACAUAUUUGGGCACUGGUUUGGCCAAGUGUACAAUGGGUCCCAAUAUCAGAAACAACCAUCCUAGCUUCCUAGGGAAGACAGUGUACAGUUCUCCAUUAUAUCAAGGCUACAAGGUCUAUGAGCAAUAAUGUGAUUUCUGGACAUUGCCCAUGGAUAAUUCUCACUGAUGGAUCUCAAGCUAAAGCAAACCAUCUUAUACAGAGAUCUAGAAUCUUAUAUUUUCCAUAGGAAGGUAAAGAAAUCAUUAGCAAGAGUAGGAAUUGAAUCAUAAACAAAUUGGCUAAUGAAGAAAUCUUUUCUUUCUUGUUCAAUUCAUCUAGAUUAUAACCUUAAUGUGACACCUGAGACCUUUAGACAGUUGACCCUGAAUUAAAUAGUCACAUGGUAACAAUUAUGCACUGUGUAAUUUUAGUAAUGUAUAACAUGCAAUGAUGCACUUUAACUGAAGAUAGAGACUAUGUUAGAAAAUUGAACUAAUUUAAUUAUUUGAUUGUUUUAAUCCUAAAGCAUAAGUUAGUCUUUUCCUGAUUCUUAAAGGUCAUACUUGAAAUCCUGCCAAUUUUCCCCAAAGGGAAUAUGGAAUUUUUUUGACUUUCUUUUGAGCAAUAAAAUAAUUGUCUUGCCAUUACUUAGUAUAUGUAGACUUCAUCCCAAUUGUCAAACAUCCUAGGUAAGUGGUUGACAUUUCUUACAGCAAUUACAGAUUAUUUUUGAACUAGAAAUAAACUAAACUAGAAAUAAAA